GAAGCGUGAUGAAGGCCUACGAGUGCGGCGCGGCCUGAAGGGGCACGCGGGGGACCUGCAAAGCUAGUGAGGGGCGGGGCAGGCGGCGCGGUGGGGGCGGGCCGAGCCCGGAGGCCAGAUGAGCGGACACAGCCCCACGCGCGGGGCCAUGCAGGUAAGUGGCUCCCGACGGCCCCACUUGAAUUUCGAUCCCAGACCGGGUCCGGCGCCCUCCGGGGCCCAAGCUUAGCGCGGUGCUGCAGUGGGGCCGCCUGACCCAAAGCGAAACCGAAAGCCCCGCGGAGGGUGACCUGACGACUUUCCCGGGACUGGAAGGGGGAGUCCUGCGAGAGACUAGGUGGCCAUGAACGGUAAGGCCCGCAAAGAGGCGGUGCAGACUGCGGCUAAGGAACUCCUCAAGUUCGUGAACCGGAGUCCCUCUCCUUUCCAUGCUGUGGCUGAAUGCCGCAACCGCCUUCUCCAGGCUGGCUUCAGUGAACUCAAGGAGACUGAGAAAUGGAAUAUUAAGCCCGAGAGCAAGUACUUCAUGACCAGGAACUCCUCCACCAUCAUAGCUUUUGCUGUAGGGGGCCAGUACGUUCCUGGCAAUGGCUUCAGCCUCAUCGGGGCCCACACGGACAGCCCCUGCCUCCGGGUGAAACGUCGGUCUCGCCGCAGCCAGGUGGGCUUCCAGCAAGUCGGUGUGGAGACCUAUGGUGGUGGGAUCUGGAGCACCUGGUUUGACCGUGACCUGACUCUGGCUGGACGCGUCAUUGUCAAGUGCCCUACCUCAGGUCGGCUGGAGCAGCAGCUGGUGCACGUGGAGCGGCCCAUUCUUCGCAUCCCACACCUGGCCAUCCAUCUGCAGCGAAAUAUCAACGAGAACUUUGGGCCCAACACAGAGAUGCAUCUAGUCCCCAUUCUUGCCACAGCCAUCCAGGAGGAGCUGGAGAAGGGGACUCCUGAGCCAGGGCCUCUCAAUGCUGUGGAUGAGCGGCACCAUUCGGUCCUCAUGUCCCUGCUCUGUGCCCAUCUGGGGCUGAGCCCCAAGGACAUAGUGGAGAUGGAGCUCUGCCUUGCAGACACCCAGCCUGCGGUCUUGGGUGGUGCCUAUGAUGAGUUCAUCUUUGCUCCUCGGCUGGACAAUCUGCACAGCUGCUUCUGUGCCCUGCAGGCCUUGAUAGAUUCCUGUGCAGGCCCUGGCUCCCUGGCCACAGAGCCUCACGUGCGCAUGGUCACACUCUAUGACAACGAAGAGGUGGGGUCUGAGAGUGCACAGGGAGCACAGUCACUGCUGACAGAGCUGGUGCUGCGGCGGAUCUCAGCCUCGUGCCAGCACCCGACAGCCUUCGAGGAAGCCAUACCCAAGUCCUUCAUGAUCAGCGCAGACAUGGCCCAUGCUGUGCAUCCCAACUACCUGGACAAGCAUGAGGAGAACCACCGGCCUUUAUUCCACAAGGGCCCCGUGAUCAAGGUGAACAGCAAGCAACGCUAUGCUUCAAACGCGGUGUCAGAGGCCCUGAUCCGAGAGGUGGCCAACAAAGUCAAGGUCCCCCUGCAGGAUCUCAUGGUCCGGAAUGACACCCCCUGUGGAACCACCAUUGGACCUAUCUUGGCUUCUCGGCUGGGGCUGCGGGUGCUGGAUUUAGGCAGCCCCCAACUGGCCAUGCACUCUAUCCGGGAGAUGGCCUGCACCACAGGAGUCCUCCAGACCCUCACCCUCUUCAAGGGCUUCUUUGAGCUGUUCCCUUCUCUAAGCCAUAAUCUCUUAGUGGAUUGAGCCCUCUUGGAAAGACUUCUCUGCCAUCCCUUUGCACCUGAGAGGGGAAGUUCUCAGCUGAGCUGAAGCUGGAUUAUUAAAGUGGAUUGUCACUCAGACUCUCCGUGCUACGCUUAUUUGGAGACUAGAGGAGUGGGAGUUGAGCCUGGCUUGAACCUUUGGAACCAGAAAAGUUGGGGAGCAGGUGGAGGAGGCCACACUCCUGGGAGCUGAUGGUUUUAAAUCUGGUUUUAAAUCUCUUCUCUGUCUCAAGUCCAUGUCUGAAGUGGGUGAAGGGUGGACUGGAUCCUCAAGCAGAAGGUCACUUCUCCCACCCCUAGUCCUCCACCUGGGAAAUGGCCUCAACGGUCUUCCCUCUUUCCAUCCCCAGAAUGGGUGUCCCGCUCUGCCUUCAGAGAUCCUGUUCUGCACUGGGCCACCUUCAGAGCUGCUCUGGGCAGACAAAGCUGUUUCUCACCCUCCCAAAAUCCCUUCCCAUCCCCUCUCAGGAGCUGCAAAGAGAAGGGCACAGUCUAUACCUUAUCACCCUUCAUCAUCCACUUCUCAGCAGUCCCUGGUAUUACUUGAUUGUGAACAUAUUAUCAGGAAAAAAGAUUAUCAUUGAAAAAAUUGGAAAAGUCAAAGUCUGGCCGGGUGCAGCGGCUCACAUCUGUAUUCCCAGCAUUUUGGGAGGCCAAGGCAGGUGGAUCACUUGAGGUCAGAGUUCAAGACCAGCCUUGCCAACAUGGUGAAACCCAUCUCUACUUAAAAAAAAAUACAAAAAAAUUAGCCAGGCAUGGUGGCACACACCUGUAAUCUCAGCUAUUCAGGAGACUGAGGCAGGAGAAUAGCUUGAACCAAGGAGGCGUAGGUUGCAGUGAGCUGAGAUGGAGCCACCACACUCCAGCCUGGGCAACAGAGCAAGGCUCUGUCUCAGAGAAAAAAGGCCAGGCGUGAUGGGUCAUGCCUGUAGUCCCAGCACUUUAGGAGGCUGAGGUGGGCGGAUCACCUGAGGUCGGGAGUUCAAGACCAGCCUGACCAACAUGGAGAAACCCUGUCCCUGCUAAAAAUACAAAAUUAGCCGGGCGUGGUGGCACAUGCCUGUAAUCUCAGCCACUCCGGAGGCUGAGGCAGGAGAAUCGCUUGAACCCAGGAGGCGGAGGUUGUGGUGAGCCAAGAUCCUGCCAUUGCACUCUAGCCUGGGCAACAAGGGUGAAACUCUCUCAAAAAAAAAAAAAGAAAAAGAAAAAGUCAAAGCCUGCUUAUAAACCAACCUCCUUCCUUCCACUAAAAUAAUUGUGCAAACUGGUGUCCUUCCAAUCUUUUUGAUACCUAUAUAAAAGUUUAUUUCCAUAUAAAUAUUCCACUUCAGCUUUCUAAAAAACUUAAUAUAAUAUAGAGAUAUUUCUAUAUCAAUACAUAUAAAUUUAAUUUAGCAAUGGCAAAAAGUUAGAAUUCAUCUAAAGAUUUCUCAGUAAAGGCAAGCCCAAAUACACUAUGAAAUGUCCAUUAUAGGUAGCUAUUGAGAAAAAGAUAAAUUGUAUAGUGUGUGUACUAACAUGAAGAGAUUACAAAGACAUUGUUGAGUAGAAAAGGCAGGUUGCAGAACUGGACACAGGACAAGGAGUACCUUCAAAACAUUAUAUGGCCAGGCACGGUGGCUUAUGCCUGUAAUCCCAGCACUUUGGGAGGCCGAGGUGGGCAGAUCACUUGAGGUCAGGAGUUCAAAACCAGCCUGGCCAACAUGGUGAAAACCUCUCUACUAAAAAUACAAAAAAAAUUAGCCAUGCGUGGUGGUGGGUGCCUGUAAUCCCAGCUACUCGGGAGGCUGAGGCAGGAGAAUAGCUUGAGCCAGGGAGGCAGAGGCUGCAGUGAGCCAAGAUUGAGCCACUGCACUCCAGCCUGGGCGACAGAGCCAGACUCCGUCUCAAAAAAAAAAUUAUUAUAUAUUUUUAUGUGUAUAUAAAUAUGCACGUAGAUGUAUACAUGUAUAGAAAAAGCCUGGAAAAAUGCACCUGAAACUUUUACAGUGAUCUUCUGGGUUGGGAGUGACAAAAGGGCCUUAGCCUUUUUGUAAUGGUUUCCUUUUGUAUAACAGAAUGUACCAUGUAUUACUUAUGUAAAAAAUUUUACCCUCACACUGUAUUUACUCUUACAAUUGGCGUACAGUAUUUUAUUGUAUAGAUGGUCAUUAUUUAUUCAGUCUGUUAAUAAUGGUCAUUUAAGUUUUUCUCCAGUUGACAACUCUAAAUAACAUUGAGAUAAAUGUA